GAGCCGCGAUGGAGCUGCACAUCCUAGAACACCGGGUGCGGGUGCUGAGCGUCGCCCGUCCCGGUCUCUGGCUCUACACCCACCCGCUCAUCAAGCUGCUCUUCCUGCCCCGCCGCAGCCGGUGCAAGUUCUUCAGCCUGACGGAGACCCCUGAGGAUUACACGCUUAUGGUGGACGAGGAGGGCUUUAAAGAGCUGCCCCCAUCUGAGUUCCUGCAAGUAGCUGAGGCCACAUGGCUGGUGCUGAACGUGUCGUCUCACAGCGGUGCGGCAGUGCAGGCUGCUGGGGUCACCAAGAUCGCCCGUUCGGUCAUCGCGCCACUGGCCGAGCACCACGUGUCUGUGCUGAUGCUGUCCACUUACCAGACGGACUUCAUCCUGGUGCGGGAGCAGGACCUGUCCGUGGUGAUCCACACGCUGGCCCAGGAGUUCGACAUUUACCGCGAGGUGGGCGGAGAGCCUGUGCCUGUGACGAGGGAUGAUUCCAGCAAUGGCUUUCCCCGCACUCAGCAUGGGCCCAGCCCCACGGUGCAUCCCAUCCAGAGCCCACAGAACCGCUUCUGUGUCCUCACACUGGACCCUGAGACGCUUCCAGCCAUCGCCACCACCCUCAUAGAUGUCCUCUUCUACUCGCACAGCACCCCCAAGGAGGCAGCCUCUAGCAGUCCUGAACCCAGCUCCAUCACGUUCUUUGCCUUCUCCCUCAUCGAGGGUUAUAUCUCCAUUGUCAUGGAUGCUGAAACACAGAAAAAGUUCCCCAGUGACCUCCUGCUGACCAGCUCCUCGGGGGAGCUGUGGAGGAUGGUGCGCAUCGGUGGACAGCCCCUGGGCUUUGAUGAAUGUGGCAUCGUGGCACAGAUUGCAGGUCCCCUGGCUGCCGCUGACAUCUCUGCCUACUACAUCAGCACCUUCAACUUCGACCACGCCCUGGUGCCCGAGGACGGUAUCGGCAGCGUCAUCGAGGUCCUCCAGCGGCGGCAGGAAGGCCUGGCUUCCUGAGGCCCAUGGGCAACAGAGCAGCCUCCCUGCUCUCCCCUCGACCCAGGCUUCCAAAGACUUCUCUAAGCUAUUUCCUUAAGCUCUGGAACGAGCCCCCUGUUCUGCUGGGGACCCUCGUUCCGCUCUCUGUAUGUAAGCUGCGUGCAGGCACCGGCUUUUACGCGGACACCUGUGUACACUCACAGGUGGAGUGGGCAGGUGCUAGCCUGACUGCGUGUCUGCCCAUGCAGGGGAACACGGUGCUCGGGGCUUAAGCCCCCAACCCAUCACUCCCUGCGCAGCCUCGGCGUUUGCACAGUCCCUGCCUGAGGCCUGAGCCAUUCCCCAAAGGCUUCCUGGGCCAGCUGCCCCGCUGACCUCCGUUCUGCCUCUGGUGGGGUUGCCUUCCCUGGCCAGGUGAGUCCUGACAGUGCCUCUCCCUCCUGGGGCCUCCAAGGAAAGUAUUUUGACAUCUCUCUCUCUUCUGUUUUUAUUGACUUGUUAAUAAAGGACUUUGUAGUGAC